GCAGUUAUCAUAGAGCACAGUCCCUCACAUCACACAGCUGCAGAGAUGAGUAAACAAAGAGGAACCUUCUCAGAAGUGAGUCUGGCCCAGGACCCAAAGUGGCAGCAAAGGAAACCUAAAGGCAAUAAAAGCUCCAUUUCAGGAACCGAACAGGAAAUAUUCCAAGUAGAAUUAAACCUUCAAAAUGCUUCUCUGAAUCAUCAAGGGAUUGAUAAAAUAUAUGACUGCCAAGGUUUACUGCCACCUCCAGAAAAGCUCACUGCCGAGGUCCUAGGAAUCAUUUGCAUUGUCCUGAUGGCCACUGUGUUAAAAACAAUAGUUCUUAUUCCUUUCCUGGAGCAGAACAAUUCUUCCCCGAAUGCAAGAACCCAGAAAGCACGUCAUUGUGGCCAUUGUCCUGAGGAGUGGAUUACAUAUUCCAACAGUUGUUAUUACAUUGGUAAGGAAAGAAGAACUUGGGAAGAGAGUUUGCAGGCCUGUGCUUCAAAGAACUCUUCUAGUCUGCUUUGUAUAGAUAAUGAAGAAGAAAUGAAAUUUCUGGCCAGCAUUUUACCUUCCUCAUGGAUUGGUGUGUUUCGUAACAGCAGUCAUCAUCCAUGGGUGACAAUAAAUGGUUUGGCUUUCAAACAUGAGAUAAAAGACUCAGAUCAUGCUGAACGUAACUGUGCAAUGCUACAUGUACGUGGACUUAUAUCAGACCAGUGUGGAUCUUCAAGAAUCAUUAGACGGGGUUUCAUCAUGUUGACCAGGCUGGUCUUGAACUCCUGAGCUCAAGAAAUCAACACAUCUUGGCCUCCCAAGUUGCUGGGAUUACUGACACAAGCCACCGCCCCUGAGUGCUCAUGUACCAUUUAGCUUGUGUUUUAAAAAUCUACUUUUUCUGCCCUCCCUAUUUUUAACUAGAUGAUGUUUUAAAAAUUACUUUUCCCUCUCUAUAUAGUUUGAUUUAAGCAUUAGUCAUUUACAACAAAUAUUAAUAUUAAAAUGCAGACCGUUAUGAUUGGAAAAUAAAUCAAUGAACAAUA